AGGCUCUCAGUUUUUUUCAUCUUUAAAAUGGGGAUUAUAUUUCCUGAUUAUAGUAGCUGAUUAUAAUACAGAUUAUGGUGCCAAUCUCAGAGGUAAGAUAAAUGCACUUAGCAUACAACAUAGAACACAGUAAGUGCUGAAUAAAUGGUACCUGCCAUUAUUAUUGCAAGCUAAUUAAAAACGAUCAUUUGUACUAAAUUAUGUUUUAUUCAAGGAAGGUAAUGUCAUUCCUCACCAAUUAAUCAUUUGUUGAUGAAAGGCCCUUGAGUAGCAAUGUCACACACUGUAUGAGAACUGGAAAGGAUAGAUCUUUUGUUACAUCAGCCACCCUGUCUCAUAGAUGACUGCUGGCUCCUCUUUUCUGCACGAAGGCCAGAACAUGAAAAGUUAGAUAUUUAUAAAAUUGCUCAAUUCAUAAUAUUUGAGAGUUGAUGAUAAUUUCUGUUUUAGCUCUUGCUCCCCAAGGAGCAGAUGCUUCUGGGGAGGUUCAGGAGCACGUGAAGAAACAACACUGAUAGAUGGCGAUCGGGACAAGAGCACCUUAUUAAUUCAGCUACCACUGUGGGUGACUGCAGGUCAAUACCCUAGGGCAACUCCAAGAGCCAGUGUAGGGUACACAUCUUAGAGUCAUCAUACACAAGGGGUGAGGGAGCUAGGUUAUUUAUACACCAACCCCUGAUUGACUAGUAAAAUGUCUCCCCUGGUCGUUUGGGUUUUUUUUAAUUUUUAAUUUUUGUAGGUACCCCUAGUAGUUGUGAUUUCUCCAAAACUUCUAACUUGCUACAAAGGAGGACAACAGAGAUUAUCCAGCCAGAGAAGUUCUUACAUAAAGAAAUGCAGGGCCUGUGUGCUCAGCAUGGUAAGGACAAGCCAGGAUAUCACAGACAUUGCCAUGAAAGUGGUAAAUGGAGAAAUACAGUCUUUGGAGGAAUCUUGACUUCUCAGCACUCUUUGUUUAUUCAUUUAAAUGUGCCUAUUUUUAUGGAUGGUGGGUCAAGAUGGCGGAUUCAAUGAAAUAGUAUUUCAUAACAAAAUGAGCAUGAAGAGAAUUUGGGCAUGUCUACCAAAACACGAAGGACAACAACAAGAGCAAGACCCAACAAACCUAUACAUCUCAAAUCUCCCCAUUUCUAUGGAUGAGCAGGAGCUUGAGAAUAUGCUGAAACCCUUUGGACAUGUCAUUUCCACAAGAAUACUAAGAGACGCUAAUGGAGUCAGCAGAGGUGUUGGCUUUGCCAGAAUGGAGUCUACUGAAAAAUGUGAAGUGGUAAUUCAACAUUUUAAUGGAAAAUAUCUGAAAACACCACCAGGCAUCCCAGCCCCCAGUGAGCCUUUGCUGUGCAAAUUCGCUGAUGGAGGACAAAAGAAGCGACAGAAUCAAAGCAAAUAUACCCAGAAUGGGAGGCCUUGGCCCAGGGAAGGAGAGGCUGGCAUGGCUUUGACCUAUGACCCCACAGCUGCCAUACAGAAUGGAUUUUAUUCUUCACCGUACAGUAUUGCAACCAACCGCAUGAUUCCACAGACAUCUAUCACGCCAUUCAUUGCUGCUUCCCCUGUCUCCACAUACCAGGUCCAGAGUACUUCAUGGAUGCCUCAUCCGCCAUACGUUAUGCAACCAACAGGUGCUGUGAUUACACCAACCAUGGACCAUCCCAUGUCAAUGCAGCCAGCCAACAUGAUGGGCCCACUGACACAGCAGAUGAAUCACCUUUCGUUGGGCACAACAGGAACGAUUCAAUCCCAAGACAGGAUUAUGAUACUCCACCAGCUGUUGUGUCAGUAUAUGACUGCUGCUGCUCCUAUGCAAGGGACCUACAUUCCUCAGUACACGCCUGUGCCUCCGACAGCUGUUUCUAUUGAAGGUGUUGUUGCUGAUACCUCUCCCCAGACAGUGGCACCUUCAUCCCAGGACACCAGUGGUCAGCAGCAACAGAUAGCAGUGGACACAUCCAACGAACAUGCACCUGCAUAUUCUUACCAACAGUCUAAACCAUAAACAGGACUGAAGAAUGUCUGUCUGAAUCUUUGCCUUGAAUGAAGAAACUUCAUUGAACAAGAAGUUGGCUUCCAGUUUGCACAGACGUCAAUGGAAUGCAUUUUUUUGUUGUUGUUGUUGUUUUUUUUUUAGUGUUAUACCUUACCCAAUGAAAGCAAAGUUUUUAUGUGCUGUGCAAAUGGUCUUCAUGUGGUCUGACAAUUUAUUUUUGCCAUCAUUUUUUUAAUUAAAGAAAAAAUUUCCAGAAGAGGAAAAAAAAACUACAAAAAACAAAACAUUGAAGGUUGAUAUUUUAUGUGGAAGAACAUUUGAAUUGAAUUCAGAAUUUUUCUGAAGGUGUAGAUACUUUUUUUUUUUUUUUAACAGAAAACCUGAUGUCAAGAGGUGGGCAAUAGAAAUGGAAACAAAUUGUCUUCCUCAAUAAUUAAGCUACUUUCUCUUUUUCCCUUCUUGUUUUAAUCUAGUGGGUUUUUUAUUUUAUUUUUUCUUAGAAAUAUGUAGGUAAGGUUUAUCUUGAAUCUUAAUUGCCUUAAUUUUAAGGACGUCAAAGGCUCUCGAGGCAAGCUGUCAACGUCUUGUUGAAAACAAAAAUCAAGAAAGAAUUGAAAUACUGUGCCGGCUUUCACUGGCACAGAAGUUUAAGACUAUGAGUUUUUAGGGUGAAGAAAAAACUGUACAGUUUAAAUGAAAAUGUUUUUCUUCAUUUGAAGAAAAUUUGUUGAUAAACCAUGGCAACUGCAAGAAUUGGAAAAAUGCUGGGACUUUUCAUGAACUUUGUCUUAAGUGUUGACAUGAAUCAUUCUAAAAGGCUAAAACAUUUUACAGUAAAGUUAUUAAGGUUGGUUUAAAAACAACUGCAUUAGAAAUAAUGCGUGUUUGGGGGGCAGAAUGCAGAUUUUUUUAAUUUACAAAGCGUGAUCGCUAGCAAAAGCAUUAGUGCUUUUUAUCUGCAGUCUUUUUUAUGAGCUUUACAAAGUUUUUAGUCAGCUUUGCUUGUCACAUUGCAAAACCUAGCUUAAGAGCAUUAAAAAAAAAAACUUAAGUAGAUAGGAGCUUAUGGUCAAAAAGUGCAAAAAAAAAAACAAAAAAAAAGCAAUAGAUAGAGAAAUUGUUGACAAUUUCUGUAGUCUUUCCUAGUUGUGAUCAAAUUCAGCCUAUGGAUGGCCUAUUUUAUACCAAAGAUGAAGUGACACCCUAUUACAGUCCAGAAGAUAGAGGUUGUUUUCGUUUCUUUUCUUUUUAAAAAAAAAAAAAUUUAUUUGACCGACAUGGCCGGACCAGUUCUUUCUUUGUUGUUUGUUUAAACUACCUUCCACUGGUGUUUUACAUAGUGCAAAAAAAAAAAGAGGGUGGGGGGAGUUGUCUCUCUUUUCUUUAAAUGUGUAUUCAUUGAUAGCAGAAGCUUGUACCUGCUGUGUUUAGCAGUUUCAGCAUGAAGAGUUCUGGAUAUGAACUGAUUCAUAGAGCCAAGUGGCUUUAAAUUCUGUGAGCUUUUCUGGUUUCUCACUAGCUGUCUUGAAUAGUGAAACCUGUAUUGAUGGCCACUAGUAAACCAAGAUGCUUAUUUAACAGGUGGAAUAUUCUUUAUAUGAAAUUUCAGCUAAAGACACUUUCUGGACCUGGUCUGAAAGGUCAUUUGUCAAAAAAGCUUAGGGAUAUUCUGUGAAAUGGUGAGUGGUCUCCUGGAAAGGUCUCAUUGUAUUUGAACAAUAGUCUUCCCUCUAAAUUACAACACCUCUGGGUUUUGUCUUUACACCUCUGUCUUUGUCAUCACCUACCAUGAAUAGUCACCUUGGUUUUGCAAAUGGGGAGGGGGUAUCAUCUUUUUGCCUGUUUUCACUGUAUUUUUGUAUAUUGGUGUUGCCGAAAGAACUUUUUCUUUCAGUUUAAUUCUUUGAGGCAUGUAGGACCAAUAAGAUUGAGAAUUCUAUUGGUGGAAUUUAGGGAAGUCCUUAAAAUGCUAGUUGACAAUCAAGGAACAGUAUGAUUUAUAUCAAUAAGAACCAAAAGAAUUAGGUUUGAUCAAUCAUUUAAGCCAAGGAGGAAUACUUGCAUUUAGAACAAUGCAAAACUUUGUCUAAAAUGAAUUAAAUUGACCCACCUGUAAAAUAUAUCUACAUUUUUAAUUCAUGAGAUGAUAUGUGUUCAACCUUUACAGUUUUACCUGAAAUUAAGGACAAUGGAAUAGAAUUUGUUAAGUGAACCAUUCACUAGAUUGCUUUCUGAAUGAAUCCUUUGAAUCAAAUAGGUGAAACUCUUUUCAAAAACUAAGUCAGUCACAGGAGCCUGUCUUAGUCCAAAAGAAGCAGGGAAAUGUAUUUAAGUGUACUAUAAAACAGGGUAGGCUUUUUAAAAACUAAAAAGUUUUAAAGGUAAAUCAUAUUCCCAUUAGGUCAACAUGAGUAAUAAGGUUGACUCAUGUGAAAUUGUCAAUAUUCUACUAUUUCUGUAAACUCUGGUUCUCUUAUUUGCAACCCCAUGCACUGGAAGCCCAAAUCAGAGAAUGACUCCAUAUAUUUAUGGUCACAUUGGAGACAAAAGUGUAUCCAAGAAAAUGUAGUGUGCGUUAUAGAGAAAUUCCAACUGGUCACACUCACCAUUAUGGUUUUUCAUGCUUUAGAGAAAAUGCUAGAUUUAUACUGUCUUUUGUUCCAUCCUUCAGCUUCCCAUGCAUUAUAAAGGUGGCACUUAAGUUUUUAUCUUUGAAAAGUGGGCCCCAAAGUUUUUUGGGGUACAAAAAGACAUGUAUGAGAACCAUAUUUUCUGUUUCUCUUUUUCACUCUCUAAACUCUUUUUGUAUAAAUAAGGAUUAUCCUGGGCAUAAUUCAUUUGAAUAUGAAACCAACAUACUUUCUUUCAUUUUUGUGAAAAAAUAACCAAAAACAUGUAUUAAUGUGAUACAAAGAAAGUCUCAUUCACACAAUCAACAAUGAGGCUAAGAGGUAGCUACCAUGUGGCUAAUGAAUGUGCCUAGGUAACUUCCUGUUUCUAUUCAAAACUGCUGCUUUAUUUGUACAUUCAGAAAUAUUUUUUUCAACUAUGAAAUUUCAAUAUCAAUUUUUUAAGCCAGUUUCUGCAAAAGGAAAUGACCUGUCAUUUGAUGUGUUCAUGUGUGUUUUGUGUUUGGAUAGUUUAUAUCAUGCCAUUCUAUAAAAUGUAUGUUUUCAAACCAAAAAGAAAAAAAAUAGAAGGAAAACAACGGCACAUACUCAAAUUUGCCCUGCUUUGUCUGUUGUCUUACCUAAGACUUGUUUUGAAGAGCCAAGUCUGGGAGAGAAAAAAAAGCAUCAACAGGUAAGCAGCAUUACAUUGUGUGGUAAUAAACCAAAAUAAGUUUUCAAUAUAUACAGACAACAGAAUUCAAAUUUAAUCAACAAAAUAUAUUGUAGUGAUUUGUUUGUUUGUUUGUUUGAGACGGAGUCUCGCUCUGUCGCCCAUCCUAACUAGGACUAUAAUCUUUUUUUUUUUCUUUAAGUUGAAGUUAAUUUUCUGUGCAUUCUGGUCCACCAGAUUUUCAAGCAUUUAUUUGGAUGUUUCCAUUUUUCCUUUUGACUUUAAUAGCCAAGACUUAGCUUAAACAUCAGGAAACAAACUAAAGCCACAAUCCAAAUGAGAGAAACACUGUCUCGUCUAAACUCUAGUUUCAUGGUCAGUGCAACAGUGAGUUUUCUUUUAAUAAUGGUAUGGUAUUGUCAAGGGAGGCAAAGUGUUCAUGGUAACUUGGAGCUCCCCAAUACAUGGCCAUGUCUUCUAAAGACAACGUAAUGAGCCCAAGUGAACUGAAGGUCAUACUGGCAGGUGCUGAUGACAGUUUGUCCUUGAAUGCUGACAUGUCUUGAAUAUUGCAAAUGUCAUAAUACUCUUUUAAAACAGUCCUCUACCUGACUCUAGUUUUGCGAGGAUUAGUUUGUUUCCUUGGUAGAUUUCAACAUUUCAGAAUGUUACCUCCAAAUUUCACUUGAAUUACUUCCUCCUGUGACCUUAGCAGAUCUGUCACAUUUGAAAGCAUAUGACUCACUUCCACCCCCUUCUAAUGAAAAACUGCAUGGUGUUAAAAGCACUCUCAUUAGAAAUAUAAGGCUGAGAACUGAAGAAGGCUGUUUAAAGCAGGAAUUUCACUUUAUUUUACUAUGCCUAAAAAUACAUCUUUGGACCCCUUGCAAAGUGCUUUAAAAGUACUUUCAAUUUAUGCAUGACUCCAAAAAAGUAAUUUUUUUUUCCCAAAAAAACCUCUUUAUUUAAAUAAUUGGGAUAUUUGCUAAAUACCUAUUUUUUUUUACAGUGGCCUAAAACCCCUAUUAAUGAAAAGUGAAAUUUGAUUUAAUUAGGACUCUUGCAGUCAUCUUCACGACUGAGGAGAAGUUUCAAUAGGCUGUCUAGACAUUAUGAUGUUAAUAGGAGAUUAAAAUACAUUUGGCAAUUCAUUUUCAUUCUUAAUUUGAGUGCAUGAACCACUGCAGAUGAGCUGAUAAGCAGAAAUUCUCAAGUGGGUUUCACUAAUAAAUGUUUUUUUAUAUGAUUUGAAAUCAAGUAAAGGGACAAUGUUUAUGUACGUGUAUAACAACAUUCAGCACAUUUGAGGAAUCACACACUAUAAUAAAGCUUAAACCUGUCAUAGAACCUUGAUCUAUAUUACUUUGUCUUCAGUAAAAAGUGAAGGAUGAGAUUUUGUCUUUCAUGUUAUUGUAGCUGGCAUGCUUCAAAAUUUUGAGCUUACUGGGACUGACAGCCUCUCACUUCAAUCUGAGGGAUUGACAGAAUUUAAACAGGCUCAUUGAUUCUGUACACUCUACCCUUCCUGUGGCAAGUGAUAAUGGGAUUUCAUUAAUGAAUCAAUUUGUUUUACAAAUGACAUCCACUGUGGCAUUGGAAGACAGUUGGGUCUGACUCAAGUUUAACAUUUCUUACCAAACAUUCUUAAGUAUGAAAUUGGUCCUUUAAUCCAAAUGCUCUUGGUCAUGGCUGUCCUUUGCGGAUUACAUAGCAUUCAGGAAAGUACAAAAACUAAACACUAAAUCCCCAACUGGCCCCAAAGACCUUUUAUGAUGUGAGAGACAAGAGUUCACCCCAGAUUAAUUUCUUUUAUCAUUGGCUUUAUACUCUAACAUAUAGAUACUCUCUAUAGCAAAAAAGGGAUGAAUGGCUUUCAAUAUUCAUUUCUGUUUAUUUUUGUGAGGGAAAAUAAUAUAUCAAGAAAAUUUUCUUCCACUUAGAAAGCUUUAAAGCUGAAGUAGAGGUGCAGUCAAGCUUGGAUCUGCAGGAAGAACCACUAGGCCACUGAGUCAUACUUGAGCUUUUCUUACUACUGCCCCAAUUUCUAAAUUGUGCAUAAAUACAAUCACUCUCAAUUUUUGAAGGGCUAAUUAUCUACUUUGUGGGUGUGUUUUGUUUUUUCUUUUCAGCGUGUAGGGCUUGGGCUCUGUUUCCUUUUAUUAGCAUGUCACCUGAGGGUGGAACAAACAAUUGGAAAUAAAAUUUGAUUAUUUUAUUUCUUAUAAAGUAUUAAUUUCUUAAGGGGGUUUGAAAUCAUUGGUAAAAUUAAUAUCAGUACAUUAUAUGUCAUAAAUUUUGAUUAUCUAUAAUGUCUUUUCUUAUCUACCACAAAUAAUUGAGAGUUGGCUAAAUUCUUGCAGAAUAUAUGGGAAAAAAAUCAUAGCAAAGAAUUCAGCUUCCCUCAAAAGAAAGCUAUUUUUGUUUCCUUCACUCCACUAAAUUUGAACCAGUAGCACGGAUCAACACGACUUCUGCAAUGAGAGUAUAACGGUAGCUCUUGGUACAGUCAUAUUCAUAUUUUUAAAUCUUUCUUUGACCAAAACUAUUGCAUUGUUUUCAUUACAUUUUGACUGCGUUACUUAUUAAGGCCGAAUGACUUUGACACCCCCGUGGAUUAUUUUUAUGAUCACAUCAAAUUUAAACAAUGUCCAAAGUGUAACUUUAAUGUUAUAUUUUGUUUCAAACCCUCUGGUCUAAGAUUAUUGAGAAAGAUGUUUUUUCCUCCUCCCUCAAAUAUGUUAUCUCUUCAUAUAUAAAAAAAUAAGUUAUUCCAUGCUUUUCAGGAACUGUAAAAAUUAUUUCAAAAAGAUAUUUGAAAAAGUUUUCUCUAUUCUGGACACAAAUGCUUCCAUUUAUUUCAAAAGAAGAAGAAGAAAAAUGGAAUCUUAAUUUAAAAAAAUAUAUGUAGUAGUAUCUGCUAUGAGAUAUUCAGUCUCUAUAAAAAAAAAAAGGGACACAGCUUCUUUUAAAACCCUUGUUUCAGUCCAUAUUCAACUUCAUGGAACUUCUGAAACAUCAUUCAAUUUUGAACUUUAUUUAAGAGCAUUUUUGUACUGCUGUCUCUGACUGUCAUGGAAAGUUCUGUAAUUCUAAGGUGUUUCUGGUUUUAUUUUUAAUUUCUUCAUCUGUACCACAGUCAAAUUAGCAACCAUCUCCCCCAUCCCUUGGGCUUUCUGUAGAUCAGUGGAUGUUAGGUUUAAACUUCUGUUUUCUUUGAUGAAGCUUUCAAUAAAAAAUGAAAAUAAAAUCAAUUGAAUAGG